GAGACGCGUGGAGCCUGGCGGCGAGUGGGGGCGUGCGACGGUUACUCUGGUUACUGGGGCCGCGCCGCGCUGGCGAGAGCCGCCGCCCGCGAGGGAUGCUGGUGAGGAAGCCGUCGGGAGCCGCCGCCGCCAUCUGAGGGAGGUACCCUGGAAACCACCUUUUAUCGGUGGGGAAGUGCAGUCGCGGUGGGCGGCUCUGGGGGCCAGCGAAACGGGAGGCCUCUAAAUCUUUAGGUUGGGGCUGCAUUGCCCUGGAGCCGCACUCUUGAGUCCGAGGCCAUCUUUUGUUGGAGAAGGCGUCGGCGUUGGCGUUUUCCCGAGGUUGGGCUGUACAGUGUCUCCGUCCGCGGAAAAAGAAGCCUCUGAACCCGCGCCGGCCCGCAGCCCCCGUGCCUUCCGGCCGCUGCUCGCCGUCGCCAGAGGCUAGGCCACGUUUCCCCCAGUGCCGAGGUGUUUCUGUGACCCUCCCUCCACUCCCAUUCCCUUCUGAAAGGGCACCUGCUCUUGGUGAGAAAAGAAAUUAUAGCACGAAGAGCCAGUAUCAGAAGAGUAUCCAUCACCCGCAGCAACCGCUCAGGGAACACCAUCAAAAAAGAAAAAAAGGGAAUAUCUGGAUUUCCUGGGCGAGGAGGAGCGAGUCUGCUCGGGAGCUGUUCCAGCAGGCGAUUUUUAAAUACUGCUUUCUACGCCCUAUACAACUUGGCUUCACAUACUUUUACACUAACUUUAUAUGAUUUUUAAAAACUGGUCUGAUCGGACUUCUCGUCCUGGGACACUGUUUACUGGAGUCUGGCCGGCUCUCCGUGCUCCUCUUGGUACCUCAUUUUGGGGAGAACCUUAAACCCACUCGAGCAGAUAAUCUCCGCCUUGACCGGUGCCACCAAAGAAGCCUUGGAACCAUGUGGACUUUUCUGGGCAUUGCCACUUUCACCUAUUUUUAUAAGAAGUUCGGGGACUUCAUCACUUUGGCCAACAGGGAGGUCCUGUUGUGCGUGCUGGUGUUCCUCUCGCUGGGCCUGGUGCUCUCCUACCGCUGUCGCCACCGAAACGGGGGUCUCCUCGGGCGCCAGCAGAGCGGCUCCCAGUUCGCCCUCUUCUCGGAUAUUCUCUCAGGCCUGCCUUUCAUUGGCUUCUUCUGGGCCAAAUCCCCCCCUGAAUCAGAAAAUAAGGAGCAGCUCGAGGCCAGGAGGGUAGGUUGAUUUCAAAGCGGGCAGAUGAAUGUCUUAUUUAGGAGUAGGAUUGGGUUCACUCAAAUAUAAGUUUUAUUUGAAUUGCAAAAGGCGGCAGGUUAGAUGCUUGUAUACAUUCUCAUGUAUUUUUUAUUUUAAACUCUGCUGUGCCUUGGUUACAUCUUUGACCUUCUUAAGAAUGAGUGAAGACAUUUGUUUCAUUUAGCAUUGGUUGAGCCUCAGAUGGAGGUUGGAUAUUUGAUUAUGAAAGAUGGAACGAAAUGUUAGAAUUUCAUUUUGAAGGAGAAGAACAACCACUUUCCAUGAUGAAAAAGUUUUUAAAAAGUUCUUGGGUAAGGAUUGGAUUUGUGCCUGAGGAAGAAAGAAACGUGCUGCGGCGCAGAAAAGGAACCAAUAUUUCAGAAACAAGCUUAAUAGGAACAGCUGCCUGUACAUCAACAUCUUCUCAGAAUGACCCAGAAGUUAUCAUCGUGGGAGCUGGCGUGCUUGGCUCUGCUUUGGCAGCUGUGCUUUCCAGAGAUGGAAGAAAGGUGACAGUCAUUGAGAGAGACUUAAAAGAGCCUGACAGAAUAGUUGGAGAAUUCCUGCAGCCGGGUGGUUAUCAUGUUCUCAAAGACCUUGGUCUUGGAGAUACAGUGGAAGGUCUUGAUGCCCAGGUUGUAAAUGGUUACAUGAUUCAUGAUCAGGAAAGCAAAUCAGAGGUUCAGAUUCCUUACCCUCUGUCAGAAAACAAUCAAGUGCAGAGUGGAAGAGCUUUCCAUCACGGAAGAUUCAUCAUGAGUCUCCGGAAAGCAGCUAUGGCAGAGCCCAAUGCAAAGUUUAUUGAAGGUGUUGUGUUACAGUUAUUAGAGGAAGAUGAUGUUGUGAUGGGAGUUCAGUACAAGGAUAAAGAGACUGGAGAUAUCAAGGAACUCCAUGCUCCACUGACUGUUGUUGCAGAUGGGCUUUUCUCCAAGUUCAGGAAAAGCCUGGUCUCCAAUAAAGUUUCUGUAUCAUCUCAUUUUGUUGGCUUUCUUAUGAAGAAUGCACCACAGUUUAAAGCAAAUCAUGCUGAACUUAUUUUAGCUAACCCGAGUCCAGUUCUCAUCUACCAGAUUUCAUCCAGUGAAACUCGAGUACUUGUUGACAUUAGAGGAGAAAUGCCAAGGAAUUUAAGAGAAUACAUGGUUGAAAAAAUUUACCCACAAAUACCUGAUCACCUGAAAGAACCAUUCUUAGAAGCCACUGACAAUUCUCAUCUGAGGUCCAUGCCAGCAAGCUUCCUUCCUCCUUCAUCAGUGAAGAAACGAGGUGUUCUUCUUUUGGGAGACGCAUAUAAUAUGAGGCAUCCACUUACUGGUGGAGGAAUGACUGUUGCUUUUAAAGAUAUAAAACUAUGGAGAAAACUGCUAAAGGGUAUCCCUGACCUUUAUGAUGAUGCAGCUAUUUUCGAGGCCAAAAAAUCAUUUUACUGGGCAAGAAAAACAUCUCAUUCCUUUGUCGUGAAUAUCCUUGCUCAGGCUCUUUAUGAAUUAUUUUCUGCCACAGAUGAUUCCCUGCAUCAACUAAGAAAAGCCUGUUUUCUUUAUUUCAAACUUGGUGGCGAAUGUGUUGCGGGUCCUGUUGGGCUGCUUUCUGUAUUGUCUCCUAACCCUCUAGUUUUAAUUGGACACUUCUUUGCUGUUGCAAUCUAUGCCGUGUAUUUUUGCUUUAAGUCAGAACCUUGGAUUACAAAACCUCGAGCCCUUCUCAGUAGUGGUGCUGUAUUGUACAAAGCGUGUUCUGUAAUAUUUCCUCUAAUUUACUCAGAAAUGAAGUAUAUGGUUCAUUAAGCUUAAAGGGGAACCAUUUGUGAAUGAAUAUUUGGAACUUACCAAGUCCUAAGAGACUUUUGGAAGAGGAUAUAUAUAGCAUAGUACCAUACCACUUAUAAAGUGGAAACUCUUGGACCAAGAUUUGGAUUAAUUUGUUUUUGAAGUUUUUUGUAUAUAAAUAUGUAAAUACAUGCUUUAAUUUGCAAUUUAAAAUGAAGGGGUUAAAUAAGUUAGACAUUUAAAAGAAAUGAUUGUUACCAUAAAUUAGUGCUAAUGCUGAGGAGAACUACAGUUUUUCUUUUGAAUUUAGUAUUUGAGAUGAGUUGUUGGGACAUGCAAAUAAAAUGAAGAAUGAA